CUUUUAUCUGCCAGCUCCGCCGACCCGGCCCCCGCGGCCCUCCCAGCUCGGCUCCGGCUCAGGUACGGGGCUGCCAAGACGGGGAGGCCUGGCUGGCCGCAGACGAGGGUGCUCUCCACGGGGCGCGGCGGGGCUGCGGGGCUGCGGGGCUGGACGUGGAAAGAGCAAGGCUCCGCGGGGCAGGGGCGGACUUGGGACCCGGGGAAGACAGGCAGGACGCGGAGCCGGAGGGGAGCACCUGGGCUAAGUGAGAGGACGCCCGCCCGGGGAAGCAGCCAGCGGAGGGCGCAGGAAGGAGGAGCUCGCUGGAUGGGGGCGUCUUGGGAAGGGUGGGAGGAGCAGAAGGAGCACGGCUGAGGAGGAUGCGGAUGGGGGCCUGAGAGCCUGUUUGUCCAGUGAGCAGGGGAGGGGAGGGCUGCUUGGAGAAAAUGAAGGAUGGAGGGCAGGGAGUGGGUAGGGGCGUCUGGCCCGGGCAAGGCCGCUGCCUUCCUGGAGCAGGACAGUCAGGGAGCUCACUGCUUUCUGGAGGAGGAAUGUAGGUGAGACCGGGACAGGAAGGGGUAUGGGUGCCCAGAACCGGCUGAUGUGAAGGAGUCCCACUUAGGGAUCCAGGAACAGUGGGAAUAGCACUGCUGGGGGCCAAGAGGGGCACUUGCUCCAUGGGCCCAAGCAGUCUAGACACCUUGGGGGAUGAGGGAGCCUCCCCUGGUGUCAGGAGAGCCUGGGGGUCCCCCACACACAGUGAGGGAAGGGGAAAACCCACAGCACUUGCCUCAAGGCUGCAGGUUUUGAAGACCUUCAGAAAUUUCCCUGUAGCAGCCCCUGGAGGAGGCCUGUGGGGCUAGGUCAAGCCAAGGCCUCGGAGUCUGAACAGUUCGAUGGAUUCGGAGUCUGGCUGCUCCUGGGUGGACAGCCCAGGACCCCAAGUCUGAGCUCCUAUCGGAGAGAGGGACCCAGCCUCUAGUCAUGAGGCCUGUGCUACCUCUGGGUCCUUUUGUUGAGAGGCUGCCCCUCUCCAGCCUUAGUUUCUCUGUCCAGAGGGUUCCUUGCUGGUCAGCAGUGCAGCUCAGGUCCUUUUUCUGUGCCCCAUGCUGGGUGACUAUAGCUCGUUCACCCAACCUCUCUGGGCCUAAGAGAUUCCCCCUCCUCAGAGCAGCUGUAAGUCUCAGCUCCACAGAAUACUUUCUUUAAGAAUUGCUUUUUCAGGCCAUCUGUGGGAGCUCACACUUAUAAUCCCAGCGCUUUGGGAGGCUGAGGUGAGAGGAUGGCUUAAGCCGUGAGUUCAAGGUUGCAGUGAGCUGAGAUGGUGCCACUGUACUCCAGCCUGGGGGACAGAGCAUAGACCCUGUUUAAAAAAAAAAAAAAAAGUCUGGGCAUGGUGGCUCACACCUGUAAUCCCAGUACUUUGGGAGGCCGAGGCAGGCGGAUCACCUGAGGUUGGGAGUUUGAGACCAGCCUGACCAACAUGGAGAAACCCCAUCUCUACUAAAAAUACAAAAUUAGCCGGGUGUGGUGGUGCAUGCCUGUAAUCCCAGUUACUCAGGAGACUGAGGCAGGAGAAUCGCUUGAAGCCGGGAGGCGGAGGUUGCAGUGAGCCGAGAUCUUGCCAUUGUACUUCAGCCUGGGCAACAAGAGUGAAACUUUGUCUCAAAAAAUAAAAAAAGAAAAGAAAAGAAUUAGGCUGGGCACAGUGGCUCAUGAUUGUAACCCCAGCACUUUGAGAGGCCAACGCAGGAGGAUUGCUCAAGCCCAGGAAUUCAAGACCAGCCUGGGCAACAUAGUGAGACCUUGUCUCUACACAUAAUAAAAAAAUUAGCCAGGCGUGGUGUUGUGUGCCUGUGGUCAGGGCUACUCAGGAGGCUGAGGUGGGAGGAUGGCUUGAGCCUGGGCAGUUGAGGCUGCAGUGAUGGCUGCACUGCACUUCAACCUGGGGACAGAGUGAUACCCUAUCUCAAGAAAAGAAAUAGUUACUUAUUUCAUUCUGAUCACAUUUUCCAGUACAAAUACAUGGAGGUCCCAAGUGCCAAAGUUACAAAAAAAAAAAACAGUUUCUGUUCAGUUUUGGAAGACAUGUAGGGACUUUUUCUUUAAACACUUUGGACCAAGUUGGGGAGUUAGCCUGCAUUGAGGGAGGUGACCCAGUUGCUAAGAGACUGGGAGGCCAGCCAGGGAUGAAAACUUUGCCUGUAUAAUCUGUGGUCACCACUGGGUGCCUGGGAGUUACCCACGGUGGACAAAGGGCAAGAGCGCUGGUUUUGGAGUCAGAUAGAUGUGCUCUGCCCUCCCGCCUCCAGGGCUGGGCUCCCAGGUUGGCUGUGGAUCCAGAGAGUUGUGAGGGAGAGGUAAAAUGUGUGUGAAAGUUCUUGGUAAACACCCAGCCACUAUAUAUUAUGAGUGGUAGCACCUAAUCUCCUUAAUGAUAUUUCAGGUGCCAUAUUGGGUCAUCCUCACUAAAGACCCUUCAAGAGGGUUUUCCUCCAAUAGCCCCAGUAUUAACAUUGGUCUGGCCUUAUUAUUUGUAUCUAAUGGGGUUAGACUUUCCCUUCCAUGCUGAGAAAAAGUUGUCUUUAAGAGAAUGUGCUGAACAAUCAGGGCCCAGAAAGGCAACAACGAAUAUUUUGCAUGCCAAGAAGGAGGCAAAAGAGGAAGUGGAAUUGUACCCAAAUAAUGCUUAUAAUAGGUGUUAUUUAGCUGAGCUGUAAGCUCCAGGAGGGCAGGGUAUUAAUAUAUUGAGGUGUUGGCUGAGCACUGUGGCUCACUCCUAUAAUCUCAACACUUUGGGAGGCCAAGGUGGGAGGAUGACUUGAGACCAGGAGUUCGAGACCAGCCUGGGCAACAUAGCAAGACCUCGUCUCUACACAUAAUUUAAAAAAAUAGGCAUGGUAGCGUGCGCCUGUGAUUCCCAACUACUCAAGAGGCUGAAGAAGGAUCACCGGAGACUGGGAGGUCAAGGCUGCAGUGAGCUGUGUUUGCACCACUGCACUCCAGCCUGGGGGACAGAGCAUGACCCUGUCUCAAAAAAAAAAAAAAAAAAAAAAAAUCCUGUGGUGUUACCAUUGGUAUGAAUUCCCUGGGCUGUUAGUUCUGCGAGGGCAGUGGUUUAAAUGGCUCUGUCACUGAGGAAGCUGCAGCGCCUGGCACAUAGGAGGCCUAAAGUAAAUAUUCUUGGACUGUCCCAGGGCCUAAGGGCCCUUGGAAGUCACUGGUGAAUUUACUCUCUCCUUUGACAUUUGGAGAAACAGGGCCAAGAGGGGAGGGGACUUGUCCAAGGUCACACAGGGAUUGAGUGGCUGAGUCAGGACGAGAAUCCCACAGAAACGGCAGAGCCAGCACUGUGCCAGAGCCAACACCUGGCAUCCAUGGCUUUGUUUUGCUUCCACAAGAGCCCAAGAGGCAGCUAUUUUAAUCCUCUGAUUCCAAAAGGAAACAAGCUCAGAGAGGUUGAGGGACUGUUGCAGAGUCACACAGCAGGUGAAUUCCAGACCCGAAAUUUCAUCCUCACAUAAAAAUGAGGCCUGUGGCGUCUCUUGAAACAGCCUGCCGGAGAGCCUGCAGAGAUUAGUGGAGGAUGUCCACCACCAGGGCAGCAGUCUUCUCCAGUUCUCCAGGCUCACUACCUGGCUGGCUUCCCUCCAGGCUGGAUCUUCCUAGGCCCUGUGGGCAUUUGUGUGGGUGAGCCCGUUGGGGCAGGGAGCCUGUCUGCUUCAUUUUCUGUGUGCCCCAGCACACAGAAUGCCUGGGUAGCGUUGAGGCUGGCAUAUAGUAUAAGCACUGAGUGAAAUCUGUGAGAUGGGGGUAACCCAGGGCUCUCCCUCUCCAUAAGCCCAUUUUCCACCACCUCCCUGCAGCCUGGUCUGUUUUGCCCCACGGGUGUUAUGGGAACCUUUGACAGUGUGUAUCCUUGGAGAGCAGGCUGGGGCUUGCAAGCCUUCGUUAAGGAGAGAGGUGAGGAGGGCUGACCUUGAGUUGAGGAAUAUGAAUUGGGAGGGGUGAGGAAGUGGAGGGGAGGGGAAGGGAGGAAGGAGCGGCUCAGGCUGACAGAGGCACUCCCACUGGAGCCCUGGAGAUCGCACUUCAGAGGUUCAGCCAACCCAGAAGACUCCCAAACCUUCUGCAAGACAUGUCCAGGCCAGACCAUAUGCCAUUUGGAUCACCUGCUAAUUUGGUUCACCCUCUUGUGCCCUCGUGCUCUCCAGGGCUUCUGAGCUGCUGGAGUUGAGGCCCCUUCCCCUGGGACUGUCACUGCUUAGCCACAUCUCUUGGGCCUGUGGGUAAGCACCAAUUUACAGGGCUCUGUGAAUUCAAAACAGUUACUCUGAAUGGUCUUUGCUAAGAACAAUUUAAUGAUUAAGUAAGGUCAGUGUCCUUGGAAGUCCAAACUCUAGCCAGAUUUCCCUGGUCUACACCCCUAGGGAUAAGGUAAAUGUUUAAGCACACAGUGAACUUCCUGAGGCCCCCAAAUCUAAUGGAACUAGCUAUUGAGGGCUAAAAGAGGAUGGUUUUUUUAGAAAACUCGAAGCAAAUCUCUCAGGCUGGGGAUAUUUCAAAGACUACUACUAUUAUUAUUAAUAACAAUUGCAAUAUUUGUUGAGUCCCUAAAUGAAGCUAAAACUUUGUUCUAAUAAAUUUAAUCUUUACAGCAACCUAUGAGGUAGAUAAUAUUGUCAUUCCCAUGAGGGAGCUAAGGAUCAGAGAAGUGGACAGGAACCACUGAAGUUUGCCUGACACCAUCAACCAGGCCCUAGUCACCUGGCUUUGCCUUUGCCCUGCUGUGUGAUCUUAGCUCCCUGCCCAGGCCCACAGCCAUGGCCAUGGCCCAGAAACUCAGCCACCUCCUGCCGAGUCUGCGGCAGGUCAUCCAGGAGCCUCAGCUAUCUCUGCAGCCAGAGCCUGUCUUCACGGUGGAUCGAGCUGAGGUGCCGCCGCUCUUCUGGAAGCCGUACAUCUAUGCGGGCUACCGGCCGCUGCAUCAGACCUGGCGCUUCUAUUUCCGCACGCUGUUCCAGCAGCACAACGAGGCCGUGAAUGUCUGGACCCACCUGCUGGCGGCCCUGGUACUGCUGCUGCGGCUGGCCCUCUUUGUGGAGACCGUGGACUUCUGGGGAGACCCACACGCCCUGCCCCUCUUCAUCAUUGUCCUUGCCUCUUUCACCUACCUCUCCUUCAGUGCCUUGGCUCACCUCCUGCAGGCCAAGUCUGAGUUCUGGCAUUACAGCUUCUUCUUCCUGGACUAUGUGGGGGUGGCCGUGUACCAGUUUGGCAGUGCCUUGGCACACUUCUACUAUGCUAUCGAGCCCGCCUGGCAUGCCCAGGUGCAGGCUGUUUUUCUGCCCAUGGCUGCCUUUCUCGCCUGGCUUUCCUGCAUUGGCUCCUGCUAUAACAAGUACAUCCAGAAACCAGGCCUGCUGGGCCGCACAUGCCAGGAGGUGCCCUCCGUCCUGGCCUACGCACUGGACAUUAGUCCUGUGGUGCAUCGUAUCUUCGUGUCCUCCGACCCCACCACGGAUGAUCCAGCUCUUCUCUACCACAAGUGCCAGGUGGUCUUCUUUCUGCUGGCUGCUGCCUUCUUCUCUACCUUCAUGCCCGAGCGCUGGUUCCCUGGCAGCUGCCAUGUCUUCGGGCAGGGCCACCAACUUUUCCACAUCUUCUUGGUGCUGUGCACGCUGGCUCAGCUGGAGGCUGUGGCACUGGACUAUGAGGCCCGACGGCCCAUCUAUGAGCCUCUGCACACGCACUGGCCUCACAACUUUUCUGGCCUCUUCCUGCUCACGGUGGGCAGCAGCAUCCUCACUGCAUUCCUCCUGAGCCAGCUGGUACAGCGCAAACUUGAUCAGAAGACCAAGUGAAGGGGGAUGGCAUCUGGUAGGGAGGGAGGUAUAGUUGGGGGACAGGGGUCUGGGUUUGGCUCCAGGUGGGAACAAGGCCUGGUAAAGUUGUUUGUGUCUGGCCCACAGUGACUCUCUGUGCACGACUCAACUGCCAAGGGCAUCACUGGCCAAUUCUUGGAUUUAGGGAUUGGCUAGGAGUUGCUGGGGUCCACUCCUGGGCCUGCCCCAGCUCCUUGCCCAGGGAGAGGGAAAGAGUUAACGGUGUGGGCCACUCCAGCUUGCCCUUCCACUGCCACUCACUGGGGUGAGGCUGGGGGUCAGCUUGGUGAGGAUUGGGGCUUCUAGAUUGUCUAGGCAGGAGGUGAAACUUAGGCCAGAGUCAGAUUUGAGCUGAGCCAGGGGAGGCCUUGGCAACCUACUUCUACUCAGAUUUCAUUGCUGGAUGCGGAAGGGGUAGGCCCAAAAUAUAUACAGGAUCUUACUGUCCCUUGAAGCCCAGCCACAAGUGUUGGAGCUGCAGAGAGACCCCAAAGGUAGUAGAUUGUGCCAGAUACAAAUGGGUCCCAUCCAGUGCUUCAUACUCCUUCAGUCACUAUCCCAGACAGUGAGCCCCAGAUCUCCUAGCUCUGGCUUCUGUGUCCCACACGGCCUGUUCCCAGCUUCUCUCCUGGUUCCCUUGUUACGGAUUCAUUUAUCCAUUCAGUGUUUCCUGGGCCUCUGCUCAGAGGCAGGUCACCACUGGGCCCUGUGGAUCAAUGCAAGAUGACAAAGGCUUUUUUUUUUUUUUUUUUUUUUUUUUUUUUUGAGGAGUUUCGCUCUUGUUGGCUAGGCUGGAGUAAAAUGGUGCGAUCUCGGCUCACUGCACCUCCGCCUCCCAGGUUCAAGCGAUUUUCCUGCCUCAGCCUCCCGAGUAGCUGGGGUUACAGGCAUGCACCACCAUGCCUGGCUAAUUUUCUGUAUUUUUAGUAGAGACGGGGUUUCUCCAUGUUGGUCAGGCUGGUCUUGAACUCCUGACCUCAGGUGAUCUGCCCGUCUCGGCCUCCCAAAGUGCUGGGAUUACCGGCAUGAGCCACUGCGCCUGGCCGACAAAGGCUUUGAUAUCAGAAUGAACUGUCAAGGGAGGUGCUGGAGAGGGAUUAACCUGUGCUGCCUGGGACCCUCAGGGUCUUAGGUUGGGGAGUGUGAAUAGGAGUUUGCAGAUGGAGAAUAGGAAGGGCAUUCCAGGCAGAGGGAAACCUGUGCAGAGACCAAGAGGUGUGGAAGGAAAAGUGGGGUUGGGGCUGGGUGGUCUGGAUUAUGGCCUGGAUGCAAUAAAGUACUGUGACAGUAGCCA